GAUUGGUGCUGUGACCUGCGGCAGCACAGCCGCCUGCGUUGAGCGCCCACGGUGGGCUGGACUUUGCACUAGGUGCUGACAGGACCGGCAGAGGUGGCCACUGCCCUCGUCCCCAGCCUGCACUCCUGGGCGAAGGCUGACGCUGAACAGGGUGCUGUGGGCCCAGAAGCGCCCAUGCCUGAGAGCGUCCAGGACCAGGCAGAGCUGGGCCUUAAGGGCCCUUGGACCAGUGUCUGUCUGCAGGGAGCCCCCGGUAGCCACUCGGAUCAGCCCGAGGGAAGAUUCUGGACGAGACCGUGGCCGUCCCCCGGGUGGCCCAUGGACAGCAGCAGGGGCUCCCAGGAGUGGCCAGGCCCUGCCCGCCCACCAUGCUGCAGUGUAGACCCGCACAGGAGUUCAGCUUCGGGCCCCGGGCCUUGAAGGACGCUCUGGUCUCCACUGACGCAGCCCUGCAGCAGCUGUAUGUGUCCGCCUUCUCCCCUGCCGAGCGGCUCUUCCUGGCCGAGGCCUACAACCCGCAGAGGACGCUCUUCUGCACCCUGCUCAUCCGCACGGGCUUCGACUGGCUCCUGAGCCGACCCGAGGCUCCCGAGGACUUCCAGACCUUCCACGCCUCCCUGCAGCACCGGAAGCCCCGCCUGGCUCGGAAGCACAUCUACCUACAGCCGAUAGACCUGAGCGAGGAGCCGGUGGGAAGCUCCCUGCUGCACCAGCUGUGCAGCUGCACAGAGGCCUUCUUCCUGGGCCUGCGCGUCAAGUGCCUGCCGUCGGUGGCAGCCGCGUCCAUCCGCUGCUCCUCGCGGCCCAGCCGGGACUCUGACAGGCUCCAGCUCCACACAGACGGCAUCCUGUCCUUCUUGAAGAACAACAAGCCAGGGGACGCGCUGUGUGUGCUGGGCCUCACACUGUCUGACCUGUACCCCCAUGAGGCCUGGAGCUUCACCUUCAGCAAGUUCCUUCCAGGGCACGAAGUGGGCGUCUGCAGCUUCGCCCGGUUCUCAGGGGAAUUCCCGAAGUCGGGGCCCAGCGCCCCUGAUCUGGCCCUGGUAGAGGCAGCAGCAGACGGCCCCGAGGCCCCCCUGCAGGACAGGGGCUGGGCCCUGUGCUUCAGUGCCCUGGGGAUGGUUCAGUGCUGCAAGGUCACGUGCCACGAGCUCUGCCACCUUCUGGGCCUGGGGAACUGCCGCUGGCUCCGCUGCCUCAUGCAGGGUGCGCUCAGCCUGGACGAGGCCCUGCGGCGGCCCCUGGACCUCUGUCCCAUCUGCCUGAGGAAGCUGCAGCAUGUCCUGGGUUUCAGGCUCAUCGAGAGGUACCAGAGACUCUACACCUGGACUCAGGCGGUGGUGGGGACGUGGCCCAGCCAGGAGGCGGGGGAGCCGUCAGUGUGGGAGGACACCCCGCCUGCCAGCGCCGACUCGGGCAUGUGCUGUGAGAGUGACUCGGAGCCCGGCACCAGUGUGUCGGAGCCCCUCACCCCUGAUGCCGGGAGUCACACCUUCGCCUCGGGGCCAGAGGAAGGGCUGAGCUACCUGGCAGCCUCAGAGGCUCCGCUGCCACCUGGGGGCCCUGCGGAGGCCAUCAAGGAGCAUGAACGGUGGCUGGCCAUGUGCAUCCAGGCCCUGCAGCGGGAAGUGGCAGAGGAGGACCUGGUGCAGGUGGACAGAGCCGUGGACGCCCUCGACCGCUGGGAGAUGUUCACGGGCCAGCUCCCGGCCACCAGGCAGGACCCACCCAGCAGCAGGGACAGCGUGGGGCUGCGCAAGGUGCUGGGGGACAAGUUCUCCUCCCUGAGGAGGAAGCUGAGUGCCCGAAAACUCGCCAGAGCAGAGUCGGCCCCCCGUCCCUGGGAUGGGGAAGAGAGUUAGUACAGCAGGGGCUGCCCUACGUCUCCUUCCCUAAGGAUGCUGGCCAGCACUGUCCAGUAGCUGAGGCCACUACUGACCUGCCAGGGAUAAAGAGGAAGGGUCUGCCUGGGUGGUGGCUCAGGCCUGUCAUCCCAUCACUUUGAGAGGCCAGGAGUUUGAGACCAGACUGGGCAACAUGGUGAGACUCUGCCUCUACAAAAGAAAAAUUAAAAAAUUAGCUGGAUGAAGUGGUUCAUGCCUGUGUUCCCAGCUAUUCAGGAGGCUGAGGUGGGAGGAUUGCUUGAGCCUAGGAGGUCGAGGCUGCAGUGGGAUGUGAUCAUACCACUGUACUGCAGUCUGGGCCACACAGAAAGACUGUCUCCAGAAAAAAAAAAGUUCUUUGGAGAAGCCACAGACCACCUGUCUUCAGGCGCCUCCUUCAACUCCUGAGUCCCAGCCAGCCGCUCCCAGGGGCCUGCACACAUGGAGAGGCCUCCCUGAUCCUGGGUGCUUCUCGUGGAGUACAAGCCGGACUGUGCUGAGGUUGGGACAGAGCCCCCUCCCCUGCAGAGGCAGAAGGAAGCAGCGUGCGUCCUGUCUCCUUCCAGGCUGUGGGCCUGCCCUUCAGUUAUUUAUAGCUGGAGCUGGAGAGGCUGGCUCAGAUGAGGAGUGACCCCGGGGGCACACAGGCUCCACACUGCCACCCAGCUUCCAAGGCUGAGUCUCCUCCCUAACGGGGAAGUGACGGGGUUUUGUCUCUAUCAUCUCAGGCGUCAACCACAUGCACACACACACUGUCACGUUCUGUGGCGCUAACAGCAUCCUGAUCCUGACGGACUUCACCGGGGCUCUCCAGGCAUCUCUUCUGACAAACACUGCAGGAGGUGAGGGUGUCUGACGUGCACUGAGGGCAGAGGCCCCCUUAUUCCUGAGGCGGCUACAGCUCACCGUGGGGAAGAUCAACUGUGGUGAUGUUUUUGGGACAGUUUCUUGGCAAAGGUGGCCGCGCUGUCAGUACCAAGUAGCUGGAGGUGGUGAUCAGAUGAUCUGUCUUUCCUUUUUUUUUCGGUCUAGUUCUGUCAGUUGCUGAGAGAGGGGUAUUAUUGCCAUGGCUGGGCGUUUGAUCUGUCUCCCUUUAGUUUUGCCGGAUUUUGCUUCCUGCACUUUGAAGCUCCUUUACGUCCCUGCACAUUUGAUUGUUGUGUCUUCCUGAGGAAUUGACCCUUUUAUUGUCACACGUACCCCCUCAGCCUGUGGUGGAGGGUCUCUGGGAGAGAGACUUCCGGUUCUGACAGCGGAAUCCCUUCGGAGUGACGAGGGCGGGGUCACAGCUCGCGCACCCUCAUCUGGAGAGAGGCAAGAACAGGGCAGCUUGGACCUUUUGUGGGUGGGUGGCUCACACGGUUAUGGAGGGCUUCUAAGAAAAACAAAAUACAAAACUAAAACUAGAAGGGCUAUGCAGGUGAGGUGGGCUGAGGCUUCCUUGUGAAUCUGACAUUGGUGGAGGCCGACUGAAGGCUCCCGGUCCUGGUCCCACUCCGUGUUGACUUCAGAGAAGCAAAGAUGCAGCUCAGAAGUAGCAUUAGGAUCUUCGUCCCGUUCUCUUUUGCGUAGCUUCAAAAAGGCGUAACAGUGACCUGGGAGGGGAGAUGAAGAGCUAGGCCUUUCAGAAAGUGACCAAUGGAAGGUGCCGGCAGAGCACCCUGCAGUAACAGAAGGUGAAAGCCGGAGCCUGGUGGCUGUUGCUGCAAACAACCACCCAAAACUUAGUGGCUUAAAAUCACCACAGUCUAGCUCAUGAAUCUGUAACUUGGGCAGAGCUCGGUGGAGACGGUUUGCCCCUGUGGCUCGACUGGAGUGUUCGUUCACACGGCUGCCAAGUGGAAUUUGGCUGGGAAUCUCAGGCCUUGGUUCCUGCCCACGUGAGACUCUCCAUGGAGGAGGGGCAUCUUCUUAGGAAGGCAGCUGCCAUACCGUGAGGAAACCCGACAAACAGGGCAGCCAGAGCCAGACAGCAGGCUCCUGGUCCCAGUCCCGGAAAAUGCAAAGGGACAAGUAUGUGUUGAUUUCAGAGAAGCUCAGAUGUAGCAUUAGGACCUUCAUCCAUACCCUUCUCUUUUGCAUGGCUUCUAAAGGGCAUGACAGUGACCUGGGAGGUAACUGUGCCAGAAUAAAGAGGGGAGACGAAAAAAAGAGGGUCACUUUCAGAAAGGGACCUGGGCUUCCUCACAAUAUGGCGGUUGCCCUCCUAAGGUGGACAUCGGGAGGGUCAGAUGGAAGCUCUGUGGCCUUUCCUAACUCGGCCUCACGUCACAGAGCGUCACCUUUCCUGCACUCCACGGCGGCAGUGACAAGGACCCCACCCCAGGUUCACGGGGAGGGGACGUGGCAGGGAAUGUGAGACAACACAAUAUUGCUGUGGCCAUUCAUGAACAGUCAGUCAGCCCCACUCGGCGUUCACUGUGGGGAUUUGGCUGGUGCACCUGCGAGGUGGCCUGACCUGUUUUCCGAUUUCCUUCAUCUUCUGCAAAAGGUUAACCGCUGGAGUGAUGCGAGAUUAAACAGAGGUGAUAAAAAUAGAAUGCCUGGCUCAUGCUGAGGGUGGGAGCCCACUGGGGUUAUGACCAAAGCCUCGGCGCUCUCUGUACCCGUGUCCUUUGACCCUCAGCUGUGAUGUGUGUCCCAAAAAAGCGUUUUGAAGUGGGAAGGAGCAAACCACUAAAAAAAACUCCUUUUAUCCGCAGCGUUUACCAACUUGCAGAUGUCAGUGAAAUUUUUUAAGACAGCUGUUAGAAGGACUGUUUUGAAAUGCAACUUUGAGGAAGAGAAAUUGGUUUCCCUCCUCUCCCCCGUGUUAGCCCCAGGUUCUGUCUGUGCUGUGGUGAAGAGUGACUUGGGACAGUCACCAGGAAAGACGCAAGGCAGAGGAGAGAGAAUGAGGGCUGCCUUCUCGAGGAAGGUCACAGCUCACGAAUCUUUCUAAACUUAAGUGCUGCAGAAGUUGAACUGAGAUUAAAUUUAGAGAUGAUGGUUUCCAAGACACACAGGGCCACGGUUCUUUCAGUUUUUAAACACGUGCAAAGUCCACUGAAUUGCUUUCUCGUCUCAUCUGUCAGAAGCCCCUGCAUUCACAAGGAUGGGUCUUCCAGCUUGACGAUGACCUCUCUUCGGAGAGCCUCACCCAUCUUGGUAAGCCAAGUCAGCGGGGCCUCAUGGAGCUAAAAAUAGUUUCAGGUCAUGACAGAUGUUAUCUGUAUUGCUGUGUGUGCGAUGAGUCUGGGGAAGCUAACACAUGCCUUCUGAAGUGGCUAGAAUACACACUCCCACGUCACAGCCAUGCUAUGAUGAAGGGGUGAGAAGCAGUGUCCCCUCUGAGGCAAAUCUCUCUUCAGGCAGCCCCGCAGUCCUCUUCCGAAAUCUCAUUCUUUUCCCUCUCUUCCUCCCCAAAAAGCCCAAACUCAUUGUCAGAGUGGGGAGAGGGGAGAAGCAGCAUCCUGACUCCUGUCCAUGGUGUGAACCCUGAGGGCACGGGACAGUGAGUGGAGCUCUGCCACCACCCGUUUCCAGAGCAUGGGUGAGGAGGGAGGGAUGCCGACCUGUUAAUAUUUGCUUCAGACCUUUCCCCGAUGAACGAAAUCUCCAAAAGCCUUAAACAUAAAAUGGCUUAGUCAAGCACGAGUGAUAAAGCUGGGAGUCCAAAUUUAGAUCCCACCAAGUUCAAAGGGGGAGGCUAGAACAUUCCAGGGACACACCUACACGCAGAGGGUCUCCAUACAGUGCCAAGGGAGCUGCUCUGCAGACCCACCAGGCAGGGACGGCCAGGCCUCGGAGAGAGGGACCGGCUGCCCUGCCCAAGGCCCACCUGGACAGGCAAGUCUUCCCUAGUGGGUCAGUCAACUCCACCGCUUAAGGGGUCCUUCCUAUGUAACGGAAUUUUUUUACAUCAUCAUCGAGUCUCGAAAUGACCUGUAAGGCAGAUGGCUGCAUCCCCACCAUAUGGCUGUGGCUGUCGAGAUGGGACUGGGAAGGGCUGGAGCCUCAGAAACGGCAGAGCGGAAGUUGAGGCGCAGUCUGUUCUUGCUUGAACCCCGAGUUCUCCCGCUGUUGUGCAGCUUUCUAAAAGCAAGCUGGAGCGGUCUGAGCAGGAAGAGAGUAAGAAGGCGCACGGACGCGGGAGGCCUGCACCCUGAUCCCUGAGCAGCCCCCACACACCGGCACCCACGCCCCUCGGUUCUGAUAACCAGGAGGCUUUCUGGCCCGUGCAGCUCCUUCGGACUCUGAGGAGAGGCCUGGGUGGGUGGCCGGCACUCUUAGGUGAGGUGCCAACGAAAACACCCCCGUGAUUGCUGGGGCUUCACUGAUUUGUUUUGUUUAUAAAAGGAGGGCGAGGCCUGCACAGGAAUAUUUUUAUCCCCGUGAAGACGGAGAGAAUCAGGGCUUCGCGACGGGGCUCAUAGACCUGAACUGGGUCUGCCUGCCUGUGUGCUGGAAGCAAACGACGGCCCGUCCUCUAAGCUGGCUUUGCAGCUCCAGUAAGAGUGAGAGACUCACGGGGGCCUGGCUGCCGUCCUGGGAGAGGCCCCGGGAACCGGCUCGCCCUGUACCCAAGGGCUCUCUGGAGCUCACCCCGCACGCAGGCUGCUCCAGAGCUGAAAUCUAGCUGUGAUCCCUGUGGGGCAACUGCACACAGAGGUGCCCAGUUUCAAGGAAACCUAAAGCAGCAGCAAAUUUAUGGCUCUUGGAACACGAGGCUGUCAAAGAUAAACACCGCAGGGUAAUCUAGGAAACACUUCCGGCUUGACUGUAAAGAGCCCUGGCCUGCGAACGCUGUUAAAAACAGAUGCAGAUCGCGGGUGGAGACGGCCGGCCGAGCCUUCCCUUUUCUGACAUCCUACAGCAGCACCUUGAUGAAUGAGAACCCGGAAGAAUGGAGGUUUAUUUUUGAACUCAGCUUCUUGGGUAGGGAGGCAAAUGAAAACAGGCUGAUGUCAGGGGUUUAUUUUAAAAAGCAAUUUCCAAGAAGCGUCCUGGGGUCACCACGCGUUCAGUCCAACUCUUCCCCGCUGCAGUGUUCCCGUGACGAUGAGGCAAAUCCAAAUAGUCACCGGAGUCGAGCAAACACGGCGGCCCCUGCCUCCCCCGGCGGCUCCACAAUGGCCCUCAGAGGGUCCGCGGCAGCCAGGCCCGUCCAACCUCCUGCCCUCUCUGAGAGGGGCCCGAGCUCUCGCAAGAUUAACCAGAGACGACACCUACCAGAUUCCACCACUGAGGCCUCCCUCGAUGCCUGCUCCCUGGGCUUUUUAAUGAACGCACUUCUGUCACAUGGAAACUGAGCCCGGCAUGGAGUCACGUGGCUCCACCCUGGGGCUCCUCUGAUGCCGAGAGCUCUGGCUCUCCUGACUGUGGGCCCAGUGUCCAUUUUCUCUCUCAGGCAGGGUGCUCUGCCCGCCACAGUGUGCCUGGUUUUCUGGAUACAGCAUGACUGAACCGCCCCUUCUCAGCAAAGGCCAACACGUCUUUCUCGAGUCCAAGACCAUCUCCCGUUCAAGGGCCCUCACCGCGCUUUGUGAGUCUGUCUCGUGGGCCUCCUUCAGUGGUCUGUGACCAGCGGGAAUGAAUGGGGACGUGUUUUGUUCAGCCCUGACUCUUGGACGCUGGUGGCAGCCGCGGGCGCCCACUCACCUGGCACGUGGACGAAGGUGAUGAGCGCGGCUGACGGCUCCCGGGGGCAGUGUGGGGUCCAGUCUGAAGCCGACGCCCCUCUCGGUCAGGCUUUCAGCAGCAGAAGGCAGUGGACUCUUCACCAUUUCUUCCAACACUUUCUCACGUAGGAGCUCCACUGUCCCUUCUAACAGGACAGGGCUUGUGCAGCCGGGCUUGGUCUUGUGGUCAGGGAGAAGCGGGCAGGCCAGGGCCGAGCUGCGUCCGGCUCUCAGGGACUUCCUCUCCCUGUGCUCUGCCCACCUGGGGUAGGCCUCUGGGAACAGGGGAGUCACAGAAACCACGGGAAACGGAGUGGGUUGGAAGAGGCAGAGAACACGCUUUUCUCAGGGUCGCUUAACACAGGCAGGGGUACAGGAGAGCUCCGGCCAUUUAUUCCAAAUGUAUGAGCAGGAAGGAAAGAGGGAGGGAAGCUGCAAGAACAGGCGACUUUUUUUUUUUUUUUUCCCCCCCAUCUGAAGUGAGAUCAAACUUCUACCACAUUCUACCUGUGCCCUUCUGGGUGGGUGGUGGCCGUCCUCUUGGGCGCCCCCUUGUGAGGGCUCGAGGCCUUUACUGGAUGGGCAGGAUGCGGGCAGCAGCUUUGUCGGCUGCCAACCCAACUCCUCCGACAGAACGGCAGGUGGCCCCUGUCGGAAGGGGGGUGUCUCUUUAUUCCUGCCAUCCUCCGGCCGCCUCUCCCGCCUGCACCACUUGGAGGCAGUUGUUUCACGUGGGGCUCUUGAUGGCAUAACCUGAUGUCUGUCACGGACCCCCAAGCAGGAGCAAUGCCUAAAGAGGGCAAAGGCCCGCGCGCCUGGCAGAGCUCCCUCCUCUGCUCCAACAGCAGAGCCCAGAGCAUCCCUUGGCCCGACGCACAAGUCCCACAAUAGCCUCUCCCAACGGGAACGACUUAGCCCUAAUUACAUGAGCUUUGAUCACCGCUCGAUUGUAUGGCACAGUUAUUUUUAAAAAUCCAGUCCAAGUGGAAAUACACCUGGAACAUUUUAUACUGCAAUGACUGAUGGACGACUUUGAUAUACAAAAUAAAUUGUUACUCAGCUUUUCUAUAAUGCUUACAUCUUACAUUUUCAUUCUCAAAAUUAAUAAAUGCUAUCAACCCCAA